GUUCUUCUACUUACCUGGGCCCGGAGAAGGUGGAGGGAGACGAGAAGCCGCCGAGAGCCGACUACCCUCCGGGCCCAGUCUGUCUGUCCGUGGUGGAUCUAAGCCUCAUCUGUAUCCUCUUGUGAUGGCGUGAAGGAAAGCCAUGGCAGAUUUCCAGCCUGGUGAUGCUGUACAGAACACAGGUGGCCUGCUUCCAUGCCUCCUCAGCUUCAAGAAACUAGAAUGAACCGAAGCAUUCCUGUGGAGGUUGAUGAAUCAGAACCAUACCCAAGUCAGUUGCUGAAACCAAUCCCAGAAUAUUCCCCGGAAGAGGAAUCAGAACCACCUGCUCCAAAUAUAAGGAACAUGGCACCCAACAGCUUGUCUGCACCCACAAUGCUUCACAAUUCCUCCGGAGACUUUUCUCAAGCUCACUCAACCCUGAAACUUGCAAAUCACCAGCGGCCUGUAUCCCGGCAGGUCACCUGCCUGCGCACUCAAGUUCUGGAGGACAGUGAAGACAGUUUCUGCAGGAGACACCCAGGCCUGGGCAAAGCUUUCCCUUCUGGGUGCUCUGCAGUCAGCGAGCCUGCGUCUGAGUCUGUGGUUGGAGCCCUCCCUGCAGAGCAUCAGUUUUCAUUUAUGGAAAAACGUAAUCAAUGGCUGGUAUCUCAGCUUUCAGCGGCUUCUCCUGACACUGGCCAUGACUCAGACAAAUCAGACCAAAGUUUACCUAAUGCCUCAGCAGACUCCUUGGGCGGUAGCCAGGAGAUGGUGCAACGGCCCCAGCCUCACAGGAACCGAGCAGGCCUGGAUCUGCCAACCAUAGACACGGGAUAUGAUUCCCAGCCCCAGGAUGUCCUGGGCAUCAGGCAGCUGGAAAGGCCCCUGCCCCUCACCUCCGUGUGUUACCCCCAGGACCUCCCCAGACCUCUCAGGUCCAGGGAGUUCCCUCAGUUUGAACCUCAGAGGUAUCCAGCAUGUGCACAGAUGCUGCCUCCCAAUCUUUCCCCACAUGCUCCAUGGAACUAUCAUUACCAUUGUCCUGGAAGUCCCGAUCACCAGGUGCCAUAUGGCCAUGACUACCCUCGAGCAGCCUACCAGCAAGUGAUCCAGCCGGCUCUGCCUGGGCAGCCCCUGCCUGGAGCCAGUGUGAGAGGCCUGCACCCUGUGCAGAAGGUUAUCCUGAAUUAUCCCAGCCCCUGGGACCACGAAGAGAGGCCCGCACAGAGAGACUGCUCCUUUCCGGGGCUUCCAAGGCACCAGGACCAGCCACAUCACCAGCCACCUAAUAGAGCUGGUGCUCCUGGGGAGUCCUUGGAGUGCCCUGCAGAGCUGAGACCACAGGUUCCCCAGCCUCCGUCCCCAGCUGCUGUGCCUAGACCCCCUAGCAACCCUCCAGCCAGAGGAACUCUAAAAACAAGCAAUUUGCCAGAAGAAUUGCGGAAAGUCUUUAUCACUUAUUCGAUGGACACAGCUAUGGAGGUGGUGAAAUUCGUGAACUUUUUGUUGGUAAAUGGCUUCCAAACUGCAAUUGACAUAUUUGAGGAUAGAAUCCGAGGCAUUGAUAUCAUUAAAUGGAUGGAGCGCUACCUUAGGGAUAAGACCGUGAUGAUAAUCGUAGCAAUCAGCCCCAAAUACAAACAGGACGUGGAAGGCGCUGAGUCGCAGCUGGACGAGGAUGAGCAUGGCUUACAUACUAAGUACAUUCAUCGAAUGAUGCAGAUUGAGUUCAUAAAACAAGGAAGCAUGAAUUUCAGAUUCAUCCCUGUGCUCUUCCCAAAUGCUAAGAAGGAGCAUGUGCCCACCUGGCUUCAGAACACUCAUGUCUACAGCUGGCCCAAGAAUAAAAAAAACAUCCUGCUGCGGCUGCUGAGAGAGGAAGAGUAUGUGGCUCCUCCACGGGGGCCUCUGCCCACCCUUCAGGUGGUUCCCUUGUGACACCGUUCAUCCCCAGAUCACUGAGGCCAGGCCAUGUUUGGGGCCUUGUUCUGACAGCAUUCUGGCUGAGGCUGGUCGGUAGCACUCCUGGCUGGUUUUUUUCUGUUCCUCCCCGAGAGGCCCUCUGGCCCCCAGGAAACCUGUUGUGCAGAGCUCUUCCCCGGAGACCUCCACACACCCUGGCUUUGAAGUGGAGUCUGUGACUGCUCUGCAUUCUCUGCUUUUAAAAAAACCAUUGCAGGUGCCAGUGUCCCAUAUGUUCCUCCUGACAGUUUGAUGUGUCCAUUCUGGGCCUCUCAGUGCUUAGCAAGUAGAUAAUGUAAGGGAUGUGGCAGCAAAUGGAAAUGACUACAAACACUCUCCUAUCAAUCACUUCAGGCUACUUUUAUGAGUUAGCCAGAUGCUUGUGUAUCCUCAGACCAAACUGAUUCAUGUACAAAUAAUAAAAUGUUUACUCUUUUGUAAGAUUAUGUUUUACUUAUCUCAAAGGAGAUACAUAUAAUUUAUAAUGAUAUGGGCAGUUGCUUCCAGGGACAUCAACAAAGCUGCUUAGAUAUAAUAUUAGAUAAAUAUAACAGACCACUCUGUAUUAAUGGAUUAAAGCCAGCUAGUUAAACAACCCUUUUUAACCAUAAUCAUGGAAGCUUUAUUCUUGCAAUAAAGAUUUUUAGGCUGGGCGCAGUGACUCACACCUGUAAUCCCAGCACUUUGGGAAGCUAAGGCAGGCAGAUCAUUUGAGGUCAGGAGUUUGAGACCAGCCUGGCCAACAUGGUGAAACCCCAUCUCUGCUAAAAUUACAAAAAAGUUAGCCGGGCAUGGUGGUGUGCACCUGUAAUCCCAGCUACUCGGGAGGCUGAGGCAGGAGAAUCACUUGAACCCGGGAGGCAGAGGUUGCAGUGAGCCGAGAUCAUGUCACUGCACUCUAGCUUGGGAGACAGAGCGAGACUCCGUCUCAAAAAACAAACAAACAAAUAAAAACACCCAUUUUUAACAAAACAACUUUAUAUAGCAUACAGCCAUGAUUCUAAAUAGUAUGAUUAUGGUUCUCAGGAUCUGACUACAUAGGUAAAAAUAUUUGCAUAUGUGUAUGAAGUGUUGGGGGAUGUAGGCUAGAAUUGUAGUCUGUGUUCUAAUUUUGGUUCUACCACCAAUUAGCUGUAUGACCUUUAGCAAGUCCUUUAACUUUUCUUAGAUUCCAGGGACUCAUUUAUAAAAUGACAUGGACAAAAGCAUCUCUAAUCACUCUAAAAGAUUUGAAGUCUAGGACCUAAAUUCUAAAUACUCUUUUGAGGAGUGACUGAGUUUUCAUUUUCAUAAUUAUGUCUCUCAGAGGACAAAUUUACAUUUUCUUAACAGAGACAUUUUCUUCUUCUUUUUUUUUGUUUGAGACAGAGUCUCGCUCUGUCGUCCAGGCUGGAGUGCAGUGCUGCAAUCUUGGCUCACUGCAACCUGCGCCUCCUGGGUUCAAGUGAUUCUUCUGCCUCAACCUCCCAAGUAGCUAGACCUAUAGGCGCCUGCCACCAUGCCCAGCUAAUUUUUGUAUUUUUAGUAGAGACAGGGUUUCAUAUUGGCCAGACUGGUCUCGAACUCCUGACCUUGUGAUCCGCCCACCUCGGCCUCCCAAAGUGCUGGGAUUACAGGUGUGAGCCACCACACCCAGCCAACAUUUUCCUCUUUUAAAAAAUAUCUUCUCACGCCUGUAAUCCCAGCACUUUGGGAGGCUGAGGCAGGCGGAUCAUGAGGUCAGGAGAUCAAGACCAUCCUGGCUAACACGGUGAAACUCCAUCUCUACUAAAAAUACAAAAAAAAUAGCCGGGCGUGGUGGCAGGCGCCUGUAGUCCCAGCUACUGGGGAGGCUGAGGCAGGAAAAUGGUGUCAACCCGGGAGGCGGAGCUUGCAGUGAGCCGAGAUUGCGCCACUGCACUCCAGCCUGGGCAAUAGAGUGAGACUCCGUCUCAAAAAAAAAAAAAAAAAAAAAAACUUCAACAAUACCCUCAGGUUGAUAAUUUUGGAUAUCUAUCUGUAUCUAUAUAUCUUGUUUACCUGGUCUCCAGAAAAAGAACACAUACACAUAUCCAUAUAUAAAAUAUGUAUACAUGUAUCAAAUCUACGUAAACUAUAAAGGUGGGAUGGCUUUAAUUAUGGCCCAAGCUACUAAGACAAUGAAGACUUUUUGGGGCUGCAAGCUACUGCUUCCCUUCUUUAUCUACUAGCCUCUUAAACAAGGCUCACUUGUGCUACAAGACAGUCCACCGUUUUGUUUUUUUUUUCUUUUUUUUGAGACAGGGUCUCACUCUUUCCCAGGCUGCAGUACAGUGACACAGUCUCAGCUCACUGCAGCUUUGACCUUGCCGGGCUCAGGUGACCCUUACACUUCAGCCUCCCAAGUAGCAGGGACUAUAGGUGUGCACCAACAUGCUUGGUUAAUUUUUGUAUUUUUUGUAGAGACAGGGUUUUGCCAUGUUGUCCAGGCUAGUCUCGAAUUCCUGGGCUCAAGUGAUUCACCUGCCUUGGCCUCCCAAAGUGCUAGGAUUACAGAUGGGAGCCACCACGCCCAGCCCAGUCCAGCUCUUAUAUGUAGCACAGGGAAAGGACAAAUACUUGUCAACUAUAAAUAAGAAACAUUGCUAAUGCAUUGCAAAGAACACUAGUUUCAUUUACUUUAUAACUUAGAUGUCUACUGGGUGAGACGAAUGUCUUUGUUCUUUAAAAAAUAGGAAAAGAGAAGAAAAACUAGCAUAACAUAAGUACUCAUUUGUAAGACUUUCUGACAUGUAACAUUAGUUCCGUAGUUUUGAGACCUGGUAGAACUGACUUUCAUAUUUGGAUAACCUGGAAAACACCCAAACACAAACUUCAAGUCUUCUUUCUCUUUUUUCAUUAUCUUUUUUAGUCUGAGGUGACACCAUCAUUAAGGAUUCGACACCCGUUUGUAAAUAAAAUGACAUCAGCAAUUACUCUGAAAUGUUUCUAGUUUGCAAAGACUUAGCAAUGUGAUGUUAUUAACCCUUCCUCCCUUCAGAGACCUGUCCUAAGCUCUGAACCACUCAUUCCUUCCACUCUUCUUACCCCAGGUGGUUGAUGAGCAGUGGUCCCUGGUGUUCCACAAAGAGUCAUUAAAGUGUUACAGCUGGUAGCACUGGUAGCAAAAAAACAAACCAAAAAGUACACACAGACACACACACACACACGCACACAUACACACACACACGCACUUGGCCAAGUGACAAAAGCUUGGCCCCUGAAAUUUCUAUGAGAUCCGAUGACCACCAACAUCAAAGCAUUUUUUUUUUUUUUUUUUUGAGACGUAGUCUCGCUCUGUCACCCAGGCUAGAGUGCAGUGGUGCAAUCACAGCUCACUGCAACCUCCACCUCCCGGGUUCAAGCGAUUCUCCUGCCUCAGCCUCUCGAGUAGCUGUGACUACAGGCACCUGCCACCAUGCCCGGCUAAUUUUUUGUAUUUUUAGUAGAGACGGGGUUUCACCGUGUUAGCCAGGAUGGUCUUGAUCUCCUGACCUCGUGAUCCAUCCGCCUCGGCCUCCCAAAUUGCUGGGAUUACAGGCAUGAGCCACCACGCCCGGCCCAUCAAAGGAAUUGUAACAACUAUUUGAGAGCACUGACAAUAAGAUUAACACUCGGUUGAUUUAGAUGUUAUGCUGGUCCUCAGGCAUUCAUCUUUAGAUAUUUUUGGGGUGGAAGUGGGGUAGGGCUGACUUAGUAAAAAUAACCUCUUAGCCCAAAGGCUUUAUUCAGACUUACACCGAUUUGAGGGGUGGGUUUGUGGAAUGCAAGGUUAGGUUCUUACCUAAUAUUUGAUGACUAAUUUAGAAUUUUAAAUGUAAUUUUAAAUUUUAGUGACUGGUUUCAAAUCUAUUUUAACUUCUAGAUUGUUCAAAGAGGUCUCAGUACAUGGCUACAAUCAAAGUAUUAGACUAGCUAUUUCUCAGCUCAGUGCUCAGAAAAAUUAUUACUGUUGAUACCUUUUUCUUUGUUUCCUGUUAAAUAAAUCACCUCUUUAAAGACA